GUCUCUCCGCAGGCCCCGGCCGCGGCGUCCUCGACAACCUAUCGAAGGCGCCAUGGAGCGACCGGCGCCCCUGGCCGUGCUUCCCUUCUCGGACCCCGCGCACGCCCUGAGCCUGCUGCGCGGCCUGAGCCAGCUGCGCGCCGAGCGCAAGUUCCUGGACGUGACCCUGGAGGCGGCGGGCGGGCGCGACUUCCCGGCGCACCGUGCGGUGCUGGCCGCCGCCAGCCCCUACUUCCGCGCCAUGUUCGCGGGGCAGCUGCGCGAGAGCCGCGCCGAGCGGGUGCGCCUGCACGGAGUGCCUCCCGACAUGCUGCAGCUGCUGCUGGACUUCAGCUACACGGGCCGCGUGGCGGUAAGCGGCGACAACGCUGAGCCGCUGCUGCGCGCCGCCGACCUGCUGCAGUUCCCGGCCGUGAAGGAGGCGUGCGGGGCCUUCCUGCAGCAGCAGCUCGACCUGGCCAACUGCCUGGACAUGCAGGACUUCGCUGAGGCCUUCAGCUGCUCGGGACUGGCGAGCGCGGCGCAGCGGUUCAUUCUGCGCCACGUGGGCGAGCUGGGCGCCGAGCAGCUGGAGCGGCUGCCACUGGCGCGCCUGCUGCGCUACCUGCGGGACGACGGGCUGUGUGUGCCCAAGGAGGAGGCCGCCUACCAGCUGGCGCUGCGCUGGGUCCGCGCUGACCCGCCGCGCCGCGCCGCGCACUGGCCGCAGCUGCUGGAGGCCGUGCGCCUGCCCUUCGUGCGCCGCUUCUACCUGUUGGCGCACGUCGAGGCCGAGCCGCUGGUGGCGCGCUGCCCACCCUGCCUGCGCCUGCUGCGCGAGGCGCGCGACUUCCAGGCGGCGCGCUACGACCGCCACGACCGCGGGCCCUGUCCCCGAAUGCGUCCUCGCCCGUCCACCGGUCUCGCCGAGAUCCUCGUGCUCGUGGGCGGCUGCGACCAGGACUGUGACGAGCUGGUCACUGUCGACUGCUACAACCCGCAGACGGGUCAGUGGCGCUACCUGGCCGAGUUCCCAGACCACCUGGGCGGAGGCUACAGCAUCGUGGCGCUGGGCAAUGACAUCUACGUGACGGGUGGGUCCGAUGGCUCCCGGCUCUAUGACUGCGUGUGGAGGUACAACUCAAGCGUGAAUGAGUGGGCGGAGGUGGCGCCCAUGCUGAAGGCCCGCGAGUACCACAGCUCCUCUGUGCUGGACGGACUGCUGUACGUGGUGGCCGCCGACAGCACCGAGCGCUAUGACCACACCACUGACUCCUGGGAGGCCCUGCAGCCCAUGACCUACCCCAUGGACAACUGCUCCACCACUGCGUGCCGUGGCCGGCUCUAUGCCAUCGGCUCCCUGGCUGGCAAGGAGACCAUGGUGAUGCAGUGCUACGACCCGGACACCGACCUGUGGUCGCUGGUGGACUGCGGCCAGCUCCCGCCCUGGUCCUUCGCCCCCAAGACUGCGACUCUAAACGGACUCAUGUACUUUGUCAGGGAUGACUCCGCUGAGGUGGACGUGUACAACCCGACGAGGAACGAAUGGGACAAGAUCCCGUCCAUGAAUCAGUAAGCUGCACAUAGUCAUAGCGAAUUUGGGAAAGAUGGAAGGAAUCAUCCAGCCUCGCGGUUCAGAGCCCAGCUCUGCCACUGUCAGCCAUGCAAGCCUCAGUUUUCCCAUCUGUAACAUGGGGAGAACAGCACUGCUCAGCCCAGAGGGCCACUGCAGAGAUUCUGAGAGAGAACGUAGGAAGCGCUGCUCGGCACGACCUGCACACGGGGAGGCCUGGCGCUGCAGCGGGCACCCUCAUCACCAUAGGGAAGGCCCAGCUGCCUCCGGGGAGGCCCGUUCUCCUAGGCAGGGUGUUGGAAAGGGGUUGGCCUCUCUGCUGCUUUCUGGGAGAGCCAAGGCCACCCCUCUGGGGUACUGACAGGGCAUGCCUUGUCUCCAGUGGUUCCCCAGGUGGGGCCCUGCCCUACCCUCUCCUCUGACCUCCACUCACUCAUCCCUUUGGCCCACAGGUACAUGUGGGGGGCAGCCUGGCCGUCCUUGGGGGGAAGCUGUACGUCUCUGGGGGAUACGACAAUACAUUUGAACUCUCGGACGUGGUAGAGGCCUAUGACCCAGAGACUCGCGCGUGGAGCGUGGUGGGGCGGCUCCCAGAACCCACCUUCUGGCAUGGCAGUGUCAGCAUCUUCCGCCAGUUCAUGCCCCAGACCUUCUCGGGUGGGCGUGGCUUCGAGUUGGACAGUGGCAGCGAUGACAUGGACCCAGGCCGACCCCGGCCGCCGCGGGACCCCGAUGAGCUGCACUAGCCCCAGUCUGGCCCGGCACGGGCCUCGGUGCAGGUAACUGGCACCUCUGCGGGGCAGUGCCCCACUCCUUUGUGCACAAGGACACGUUGGGCUCACAGGAGGAGCACAGGCUCUUGGGUGGCGAAGCCAGCCCAGGAUCCAUUACCUGGAAGGUUUCUGUACCUUGAGAGCCUGAAUCAGAGGCCGUCGGGAACGCCCUCCCUGCAGUUGAGGAAGAGCCACUUUCCUGCCAGCACAUGUUUCUGGGUCUUGGAGGUCACCCCCACCCCGCGGAUCACAGCUCACCCACGCGGCGCACACCCCUCCUGCCGUUGUCAUCUGCACCUACUUGUUCCCACCUUGGGAGAGGACGAUGACUUGGGAGGGACGCGUGAAGGGAGAAGGGGUCCUCCCAUGAGGCUGAGGAUGGCCUGAACCUGGAGCAGCGGACCAGGCAGACGGGCUGAAGUGGGGUCCCAAAUUCCAUGUCCAGAGGUGUGGGGAGCCUGCCUCCCUAGCUCCUGGCCCCUGCCAGGGGCUUACAUCAAAACACCUCAGAGGGCUGCCCUCCAGAGGCUGCACCCAGAACAGUGGGACAUGAGCAGGGGUGUGGGCUUGGAGGGUGAAGAGGAUGUGGUCCUAUCAGAUGCUGGGCCUCCUCAGCCAUAGCCCCCUGCUCCUACCCCCUGACUGGCUCUUGCGUCCUCACCUCUCACCCUCUCCUUCCCGGGAGGCCCUGGGAGGUGAUCAUUGACACCCAGCCAAGCAGACAGCUGCGGGUGCCCAAGCCCUUGCUGGGCCUGCGCGUGAGGAGUCCCACUGCUUCUAAAGGAAGUCCUGGGCAGGAGGUGGCUUUGGUGGUUGGUUCCAAAGUUGAAAAUGCUUGCAGUUUGACCUUAGAAGAAGUGGGAAGAAGAAGGAGCUCUACAGGGUCAGCUUUGUUUGAUUUGUCCAGUCUAAGAAGUCCCAUUGCCAAAGCUUUCUGCAGGAGGGUGAAUGCCGCAGCUUGGCAGCCCCUGGGUUUCUCUUGGAAAUGGUCAGUUUCCCCUCAAAGUACCCAAAGUAGCCUUGGCUUGAGUUUUUGUCCUUGCCUCCUUUUUAGAGAAGAGGGCAUUUAGACUGCAUUUUCCUGGUUAAAGAAGGUUAAAGCAAAUGUUUAUUGCCUUUUCUAGUGAACUAACUCGUAGAGAUGUUCUCAGCAGGAAGACAGUCUUAGCACUGUCACUUAGCAGAUUGCACUUAAGUCCCUUGUGCUGGCCAGAUGGCGUGGCUGGUUGCCUUAAUAUGUCCCAGGACCCCUGACAGGGCUGCCUGGCCUCUCCCUCGUGCUCCUCAAGAGCCCAGUCCAUACACUGUGGAUGUCAUUGCUGUCGGGUUAGGAAGUCUUGUCCUAGAACGCCCUGGCUGGUAUGACCACAGUUCAUGGCGGCUCUUCUCGCUUGGGUCAUGGUCAUCUUCCAGCACCUGCUGUGCUGGGAAGGCCGAGGAUGGGGGCCCAGCACUGUCCAGGCCUGCUGGGGCCUGGCUGGGAGUCCUGUGGGCAGCAUGGAACAUGCAGCUGGGCUUCCUGUGACCAGGCACCCUCUGGCACUGUUGCUUGCCCUGUGCCCUGGACCUUUUCCUGCCCUUCUCCUUCCUCUGCUCCCUUGGGGCUACCCCUUGGCCCCUCCUGGUCUGUGCAAACUCCCUCAGGGAGCCCCCCUGCCCUGUAGCUCUCGCUUAACUUCCUAGGGGCUGCUGAGCCCACCCAGAGGUUGUUGGAGUUCAGCGGGGCAGCUUGUCUCCCUUGUCAGCAGGGGCGUAAGGGCUGGGUUUGGCCAUACAAGGUUGGCUACGCCCUCAAUCCCUGACCGUUCCAGGCACUGAGCUGGGCACCCACGGAAGGACAUGCUGUCCAGACUGUGAUGACUGCCAGCACAGGGCAUCUCGGGCUUGGCUGGUCUGCGAGGCCUUGCCCCUGUGGAACUCUGGGUUCCUGUUUUCUCAGUCUUUUUUGCGGCUUUGCUGUGGUUGGCAGCUGCCGUACUCCAGGCUUGUGUCGGCCACUCAGAUGAGGGCUGUGGUGCGAGCCAGUGCAGGAGAGCUGCGCUUGGGAUUGUGCCCUCUCCUGUGUCUGUCCUCCGGACCUACCCAGGUCUCCACCAUCAGGACCCUGUCUUUGGGUUUAGAAGACCAAGUAUGGGGAAAACCAGGCACCAGCCUCUGCAGCAAUGGGUCCCUCUAGCCUGUGGACACCAGCUGGGGGAUCCAGGGUCAGGCCCCCUCCUCUCCCCAGUUUCCCUCUGCUGUGGGUUCUGGGCUGUCAUGUCUCCACCACUUAAGGAUGUCUUUACACUGACUUCAGGAUAGAUGCUGGGAUGCCUGGGCAUGGCCACAUGUUACAUGUACAGAACUUUGUCUACAGCACAAAUUAAGUUAUAUAAACACAGUGACUGGUAUUUAAUGCUGAUCUACUAUAAGGUAUUCUAUAUUUAUAUGACUUCAGAGACGCGUAUGUAAUAAAGGACGCCCUCCCUCCAGUGUCCACAUCCAGUUCACCCCAGAGGGUCGGGCAGGUUGACAUAUUUAUUUUUGUCUAUUCUGUAGGCUUCCAUGUCCAGAAUCCUGCUUAAGGUUUUAGGGUACCUUCAGUACUUUUUGCAAUAAAAGUAUUUCCUAUCCA